GGGACUCUGCGUGAGGCGAGCGCCGGGGCUCCCGGAGCGGGUGAGGCGACCUCCGGGAGUGGGGACACCCAGCCCCGGUCUCCCUUAUCGGGGCCCCCUCUGGCCGGCUGGGCCCGGGAGCCCCUCUAGCGUCCUCUGCCCACACCGGCCCGAAGCCCACGGGCGGCCAUUGCCUGGGUUGCGUUUUCCGUGGCGGGGAAGCGCCGGUCCGUACCCACGGGAGACCCCACGCCCUCCACGCGAGGACGCCCCGCGCCUCCUCCCCACCACAGUCACUGUCUGCAAACCGUCUGGCCCGGGGCUGGGGAUCCGAGUGAGGCGAGGGGAGGGACUGGGAAGAAGAGGGGGAAAGUGGGGCAUCCGUAGGGCGUGGAGGAGAGCGGUCCCAAGCCCUGGGGCCCUAGGCUUCUCCGAAAGGCCGUCCGUUCCCAUCACCCGAGGGCUGUAAUCCCUCCCGCGGGUGCGGAAGCUUCCUCAUCUCCCUACCUCCCACUGCACUGCCGGUUUCCCUGGGUUACCAAGGAGAAGCCAGCGCCUCUACACCCCAGGCUUGAUUCCCUCCCACCGCAAACAGACCUUGUACGUGUGGAGAGAAAUGACUUCCAGCAGCAGGAGAUCCAGAUCCUUCAAGGACAUAUGUCCUUCUGUCUCCCUCCACUUGGACAAAUCUCAAGAAGGACUCCGAUUGGCUUAUAUCAGAUAGCCACCCCCCAACAAGUUGCCCUGACCAAUAGACACUCCUUUUGGCCAGAAUCUAUUAUCAGAAGCCAGUGGAGCCGCCCCAAACACCAGCUACCUCGCCUAAAGCAGACCUACCACUGGGCUAGAAAUUGGAGACAAAAAUGAGGAGGAGACAGCCCCUACACCUCAAGAAGCUCACAGUCUAGUAUCCCUACCUGUUUCAAGGACCUGCCAGUCUGAGAAGCUUCUUGUCAUAAGGCCAUCCAGGGGCCACGCACCCCUACCUUGCCAGCCUCCAGCAUGCAGGAUACCGUAACGACAUCAGCAUUGUUGGACCCCAGCCACUCCUCAGUCUCCACCCAGGACAAUUCCUCCACUGGAGGACACACUUCAAGCACAAGCCCACAGCUCUCAAAGCCUUCAAUCACACCAGUCCCUGCAAAGUCCAGGAACCCACAUCCCAGGGCCAAUAUCCGUCGGAUGCGCCGGAUCAUUGCUGAGGAUCCUGAGUGGUCACUGGCCAUCGUGCCCCUCCUCACAGAGCUCUGCAUUCAGCACAUUAUCAGGAACUUCCAGAAAAACCCUAUCCUGAAGCAGAUGCUCCCGGAACACCAGCAGAAGGUCCUGAACCACCUGUCCCCUGACCUACCACUGGCUGUGACCGCCAACCUGAUAGACAGUGAGAACUACUGGCUCCGCUGCUGCAUGCAUCGCUGGCCCGUGUGCCACGUGGCCCACCAUGGCGGCAGCUGGAAACGCAUGUUCUUCGAGCGGCACCUGGAGAACCUGCUAAAGCACUUUAUCCCAGGCACCACAGACCCUGCGGUGAUCCUCGACCUGCUGCCGCUCUGCCGGAAUUACGUGCGCAGGGUCCACGUCGAUCAGUUCCUUCCGCCGGUGCAGCUCCCGGCCCAGCUCCGGCCGGGCGACCAGUCCGACUCAGGCAGCGAGGGAGAGAUGGAGGAGCCCACCGUUGACCACUACCAACUGGGCGAUCUGGUAGCUGGCCUGAGCCACCUGGAGGAGCUGGACCUGGUGUACGAUGUCAAGGACUGCGGCAUGAAUUUCGAGUGGAAUCUCUUCCUCUUCACCUACCGUGACUGCCUCUCCUUGGCAGCCGCCAUCAAGGCAUGCCACACCCUCAAGAUCUUCAAGCUGACCCGAAGCAAGGUGGAUGAUGACAAGGCACGCAUCAUAAUUCGAAGCCUUCUGGACCACCCAGUCCUCGAGGAGCUGGACUUGUCACAAAACCUCAUUGGAGACCGUGGUGCACGAGGUGCUGCCAAGCUGCUGAGCCACAGCCGCCUGCGUGUGCUCAACCUGGCUAACAACCAGGUGCGUGCACCCGGUGCCCAGUCCCUGGCUCACGCUCUGGCACACAACACCAACCUCAUUUCCCUCAACCUACGUCUCAACUGCAUCGAGGAUGAGGGUGGCCAGGCUCUUGCCCAUGCCUUGCAGACCAACAAGUGCCUCACCACGCUGCACCUCGGUGGCAAUGAGCUGUCUGAGCCCACCGCCACACUCCUGUCACAGGUGCUCGCCAUCAACACCACACUCACCAGCAUCAACCUGUCCUGCAACCACAUCGGGCUGGACGGUGGGAAGCAGCUCCUGGAAGGCAUGUCAGACAACAAGACCCUCCUGGAAUUUGACUUGCGCCUGUCAGAUGUGGCCCAGGAAAGCGAGUACCUCAUUGGCCAGGCCCUCUACGCAAACCGAGAAGCAGCCCGCCAGCGGGCCCUGAAUCCCAGCCACUUCAUGUCAACCAUAACUGCCAAUGGCCCUGAGAACUCUGUGGGAUAAAAUGACCUGACUUGGAUCAUGGCCCCAGCCCCAUCCCUCAUUUCAUACCCCUGCCAUGCCUGCUGCAGAGUAUCACACUGGUUCAGAGGGAGCGGGGAGGGGGACUGUGAAUAACCUUGGAGUGAUCAAGGGUUGUAUGGAUGGAGACAUGAGGCAGGGAAGGGAGCCUGGCAUGGGGGAAGAAAGGGUAUGCAGUAGGGACCCAGCCUUUGUGCCCAGGGAAAGGAUAUUACUGGACACCCACAAAUGACCAACUUCUUUCAGGAACAGGGAAGUCAGAGAGGUGUCUGAGGGACUGUGCCUGCCAGAUUCUCCCGUUGGGGCUGCCUGCCUCCCUGACUCCCCACCAUUUUCUUCUCUACCAAACAGAUCCUUGAUCUUCAAACACACACACACACACACACACACACACACACACACACACACACACACCCUCUGGCUACAGCAGGGCUAUGCCUGGCUCUCUCUGCCACCCUCAUCCCUGUAGAUGCAUUUCCCUGUUGCUUGACUCUGCUUUAAGUGAUCCAGUUCUACAGGCCACGCCAUCCCCUAGUUCCCCAACUCCCAACCUGGGAAGGGGACAAUGAGCUGACACCAGGGGCUCAGACCCAGUGGACUCCUCUGGGGAGGCAACUGUAGAUGACAACUUCCAGGGAAGGAUGACACAAUCCCUGCCACCCACCCCAGAGAGCUUCCCUGGGAGGGAGGGAAAGAAGUGCCACACUGGGACAGGAAGUCAGUGAGUCAUCCACGACUUUAUUAUCCACCAGUUUGAUUUGUACAAUCUUUGCGCUUAAAUCCACGACAAAAAGGCCACAGUGUGAUGCACCCAAUUGACAGAGACCUGUCUUCUCCCCAGCCAGGCCCAGCCCACCCCACAAGCCCUUGUCCCCAGGACACAUGGAGCCUUCCAGGUGCCCUACAUGAGUCCCCCAUCACUCUGUAGCUGUCCACCCUGGGGCCACACCUACAGGAAUCACAUCAGCCCCCAGGGCCACAAGAGACCUAGCUGACUGAUUCAGGCUGAGCGCCAUUGCCCAUCCUCCUUGGGCUGAUUCAUUGGCCCAGAGCCUCCAGAACUGUGUCCCCAAAGGGCAGGUCAUGGGCUACAACCCCAGUCCAGGAGUGCCUGCUCUCCAGGGACUCCUUCCGCUAAGCAGGCGCUGAGCAGAGCACCAAAGGGGGCUUGGGAGUGACUGCAUGUGUGUGCCUGUCUAGGCAACCUAGAGUCUGUCUGUGCCUGACACCCUCUGACAGUUCCGGAGUGCAAACGUGUAGGUGUGAGGGUGUGUGUGUGUGUGUGUGUGUGUAUAGCCACAGCUGCUAGCAGAAGUUCUAAUUAGAGAAACAAGAACAUUCAGUGUAAAGUUUAAUUUUAGAGAUUAAUUAAUUUUCUGGUUUUCAUUUUCCCUGGCAAUCAGUAAAGCUACCAAGAAAAUAGACCAAA